AUCCCGCGCCGACGGGGCUGUGCCGGAGCAGCUGUGCAGAGCUGCAGGCGCGCGUCAUGGCUGCUUUGAGACAGCCCCAGGUCGCGGAGCUGCUGGCCGAGGCCCGGCGAGCCUUCCGGGAGGAGUUCGGGGCCGAGCCCGAGCUGGCCGUGUCAGCGCCGGGCCGCGUCAACCUCAUCGGGGAACACACGGACUACAACCAGGGCCUGGUGCUGCCUAUGGCUCUGGAGCUCAUGACGGUGCUGGUGGGCAGCCCCCGCAAGGAUGGGCUGGUGUCUCUCCUCACCACCUCUGAGGGUGCCGAUGAGCCCCAGCGGCUGCAGUUUCCACUGCCCACAGCCCAGCGCUCGCUGGAGCCUGGGACUCCUCGGUGGGCCAACUAUGUCAAGGGAGUGAUUCAGUACUACCCAGCUGCCCCCCUCCCUGGCUUCAGUGCAGUGGUGGUCAGCUCAGUGCCCCUGGGGGGUGGCCUGUCCAGCUCAGCAUCCUUGGAAGUGGCCACGUACACCUUCCUCCAGCAGCUCUGUCCAGACUCGGGCACAAUAGCUGCCCGCGCCCAGGUGUGUCAGCAGGCCGAGCACAGCUUCGCAGGGAUGCCCUGUGGCAUCAUGGACCAGUUCAUCUCACUUAUGGGACAGAAAGGCCACGCGCUGCUCAUUGACUGCAGGUCCUUGGAGACCAGCCUGGUGCCACUCUCGGACCCCAAGCUGGCCGUGCUCAUCACCAACUCUAAUGUCCGCCACUCCCUGGCCUCCAGCGAGUACCCUGUGCGGCGGCGCCAAUGUGAAGAAGUGGCCCGGGCGCUGGGCAAGGAAAGCCUCCGGGAGGUACAACUGGAAGAGCUAGAGGCUGCCAGGGACCUGGUGAGCAAAGAGGGCUUCCGGCGGGCCCGGCACGUGGUGGGGGAGAUUCGGCGCACGGCCCAGGCAGCGGCCGCCCUGAGACGUGGCGACUACAGAGCCUUUGGCCGCCUCAUGGUGGAGAGCCACCGCUCACUCAGAGACGACUAUGAGGUGAGCUGCCCAGAGCUGGACCAGCUGGUGGAGGCUGCGCUUGCUGUGCCUGGGGUUUAUGGCAGCCGCAUGACGGGCGGUGGCUUCGGUGGCUGCACGGUGACACUGCUGGAGGCCUCCGCUGCUCCCCACGCCAUGCGGCACAUCCAGGAGCACUACGGCGGGACUGCCACCUUCUACCUCUCUCAAGCAGCCGAUGGAGCCAAGGUGCUGUGCUUGUGAGGCACCCCCAGGACAGCACACGACGGAGUCUGGCUCUGUCACCCUGUCUGGAGUGCGGUAACACGAUCUCGGUUCACUGCAACCUGCGCCUUCUGGGUUCAAGUGAUUCUCCUGCCUCAGCCUCCUGACUAGCUGGGACUACAGGCAUGAGCCACCAUGCCUGUCUAAUUUUUAGUAGAAACGGUUUCACCAUGUUAGCCAGGCUGGUCUUGAACUCCUGACCUCAAGCAGUCCACCUGCCUCGGCCUCUCAAUGUACAAAAUAAUCUUUUAAAGUGCUAUCUGAAAUUCA